AGAAGAGAAAAGUAAGAAGCUAAUGAAUGAAUGUGAUCAUUUAAAAGAAAGUCUCUUUCAGUAUGAGAGAGAGAAAGCAGAAGGAGUAGUGGUUGUGAGACAACUUCAACAAGAAGUGGCUGACAGUGUAAAAAAAUUAACGACGUUAGAGUCUCCACUGGAAGGUAUAUCACGUUGUCACAUUAAUUUGGAUGAGACAUAGGCCUCAAAGAAGAAAUUAUUUCAAGUGGAAAGUCAAAUAUAAGAAACUCCUGGAAAUGACAAUAAAUAUGUUAAAUGUAUUUGGAAAUGAAGAUUUUGAUUGCCAUGGAGACUUAAAAGCAGAUCAACUGAAAAUGGAUAUUCUGAUUAAGAAGCUAAAACAGAAGUUUGAUGAUCUUACGGCAGAGAAGGAAGCUUUAUCUUCAAAAUGUGUCAAUUUGGCUAAAGACAAUCAAGUUCUUCAACAGGAGUUUUUAUCUAUGAAAAAAGUACAACAGCAAUGUGAGAAACUUGAGGAGGAUAAAAAGAUGUUGAAAGAAGAAAUAUUAAAUCUUAAGACACAUAUGGAAAACAAUAGGGUAGAACUUAGUAAACUACAAGAAUAUAAAUUGGAGCUAGAUGAAAAGGCAAUGCAGGCAGUAGAAAAAAUAGAAGAAAUCCAUUUACAGGAACAAGCACAAUAUGAAAAACAAUUAGAGCAGUUAAACAAGGAUAAUAUGGCUUCACUAAAUAAGAAAGAACUCACACUUAAAGAUGUGGAAUGUAAAUUCUCAGAAAUGAAAACUGCUUAUGAAGAGAUUACAACCGAAUUAGAAGAAUAUAAGGAAGCCUUUGCAGCAGCAUUGAAAGCUAACAAUUCCAUGUCAAAAAAAUUAACAAAAUCAAAUAAGAAAAUAGCAGUGAUCAGCAUGAAGCUCCUUAUGGAGAAAGAGCAGAUGAAAUAUUUUCUCAGCACUCUUCCUACAAGGCGAGACCCAGAGUCACCUUGUGUUGAAAAUCUUACUAGUAUAGGACUCAACAGAAAAUAUAUUCCCCAAACACCCAUAAGAAUUCCUAUUUCAAGCCCACAGACUUCAAAUAACUGCAAGAACUCCUUGACUGUGAUGGAGCUGGACUGUGUAGAACAAAUAACUAGAGAAACAAAGAGAAUUGUUGCUGUGUUGAACACUUGCUCCCGUCUACUUACUUCUCUAUAAUCCACUGCCAUGGAAUGAGUGAUUUUUCUUAGAAGCAGAGGUGGAGCCACUGAGGAAGCACAGGCGAGCCCUCCCCAGCACGUGAUCACUGGUCCCCAACAGAACAACCGCUGCCGCAUCCAUGAGGCUCCCAUUGUGGUGGGUUGUGUCACCCCACAAUGUUACUGUUGCUGAGCCCCCAUCGCCUCUGUGUUGUGGAGCAGUUAGAGACACACUGUGGUGUCUGAGUGGCUCUGCAUGAAGGACCGUUUUCUAGGUGAGAGGCACAUCUCAACACAGCUGACUGAUCAGACUCAGUCACCCCCGUGAUUACCCAGGACAACCCCAUCAGGCCCUCUCACCCAGGCCCAGUCCAGCUCCAUGAUAACCAAGACGCAGGUCCAGAGACAACCGCCCUGCAUGGUGCCUGCAUCUGACCCCCUUGGUGGGUAGUGACCAGCACAACAUGGAAGAAGUCAGGGCAGCAUGCAGCCAGCUGCCCUGCAGCCCCAGAUGGCUCCUAGGCCUUGGGAAGUCAUUCUCAAAGGGGAAGCUGGUCAUUUUGAGGUCCCUGGAGGGAAGGGUGAAUGUGUCAUCCCAACAGCCCUGGAAGCCAGCAGCAUGCCAUACAUCUUACCCAACCUGUGUGACAGAGGCCCCCUCCUGGGGCACAAGUCCCAUACCUAAAGGGUCCUGUCCCAGUUGAACCUCAUCCUGAGCCCUGGGAGGGGAGGAGCACCAUGGGCCUCCCUGCAGCAGCCAGGGUUACCACCCAGGGGACUCAGCCUUCUGUGGCCCUGGCCAGACUUAGAAUUUGGCCCAAGACAAGACAAGCUCACUCGGAGCAGCUUGUCAGUACCCGGGGCCUGUGCAUGCCAAGUAAGUCCAAGCUGGCUCAGAGCAACCAGCCACCUCUGCAAGGGUUUGCCAGGAGCAGGUGGACCAGCCACCAACCUCACCGACUCAAGGAAACAGGGAUGGCCAGGUUCCCACACCCCGAGUGACCACCACCUGACAGCUGAUGGAGUGGAGGCCUGAGGAAAAGCAGAUGGCACUGGGGCCCUACCUCCAGGGCAGAGUAACUGAUUUACUGCAAGUGAGGUUGGUGGCUGGUCCACCUGCUCCUGGCACACCCUUGCAGAGGUGGCUGGUUGCUCUUUGAGCCAACUUGGCCUUGCCUGGCAUGCACAAGCCUCAGUUCAACAACUGUGCUGCAAAUGGAGCCACAUAGAGGAAAUGAGCAGCAGGCUCAGGAGCAGGGUUUGCGCUGCCUUUGGGGCUCCAAUCCAUGCAUCGGGGCUCCAAUCCAUGCAUCAGGGCUCCUACAGCACUGUGGGCUUCUUGGGUGCCAAGAGGCAGACCACAGGCCCUCUUGAGGAGGAUUCUAUGUUCAAGUGCAGAAAGGGCCCAGUCUGGUAGAUGAACCACACGGCCAGCUUCUGGGUGCAGGCACAGUGCCACAUCUUCCAUCACUUCCUGAUGUGCCACACCAGCACUGAAGAGACAGCCUGGAGACAGGGCAAGAGGAAGGCUGAGAAGGAUGAGAUGGUGAGUGCCAGAUUCUCCCUGGCUCUGAGCCCACCUCCAGGGUGACACUCAAACUUUAGGAGUGGGAGAGCAAGAUUGACAGCUUCAAAUGCUUCACCAAGAAGAUGGACAACAGGGCACUCAGCUUAACUUCACAGCCAAUGAGUUGACAUGCAAGCAGGUGAUGGUGACAGGCUUUAAGAAAGAGCAUCAGAAGGCUGCCAGUUCUUCAGCCUCAGCCAGGCCUUGGAGCUGGACCAGCCCAUCCACUUCACCACAGAUGCCUUCAACACUGUCAGUGAGCUCUUUGCCAAUCAUCCCAGGCAGAACCUGGACCCAGUCAUGGACCUGUUAGUACUGUCUCAGGGACACCAGACCAACAUCCUGAACAUCAUCCACAUACACAAGCAAGUUCUUACCAAAGUCGCAGAAGGCAGGCAACAUGUGGCAGAAGGGAAGAUAGAGAUGCAGAGGCUGAUGACAUCAGAAUCACAGGAACAGGAAUUCUUUCACCACUUCAGUGGAAAUUCACCACUUCCAUCCAAUUUGAAUGAGAGACAUGAAAUCACAGAUGCAGCAUUUCUUGCAAAAAGAGAUACUAUUUUUUCAAAAAUCAUCCAGGAAUUGAUAGUGUUGAAUUACUAGAUAUUUGAUUGUGGACUGUUUACAGUUCAAGGAUACUUUCUACACAGAAUAAUAACACUAGCAAGGAGCUAGUGCCAGCUAUCCGUGGUAGCACAAGGAUGGUUUUGUGCUCAACUGAAAUCCAGCUGAAUACAGAAUUGUGUAGGAAACAGUUAAUAUGUUGACAGAAUAGAAACAGUAGCAAACACAAACUAAAUCAUGCCAUGAAUGCCUAAACUACCAAUGUAACUUUUGGAAGAAUGAUAAUACCACUUUACUGCUUUUUGAAGUAUGAAUAUUUUAGUGUAUAUGCCGUAGACCACAAACCCUAUAAAGAGUCCCAAAUAAGUUGGCUGGAUAAAGCCUGCUGUGCAUGUCUUUAUACUCAAAGACUGAUGAUGCAAUUCGAAUAUGUGUCCCCACCAAAUCUCAUAUUUAAUUAUAUUUCCUAAUGUGGAAGGUGGAUCCUGGUAUAAGGCAAUUGAUUUAUGAAGGCAAAUUUCUCAUGAAUGGUUCAGCACCAUCCCCUUGUACCAUCCUCACAAUCAUGAGUGACUUCUCGUGAGAUCUGGCUACUGAAAACUCUAUGUCACCUCCCUACUCUGCGUGUUUUCCUCUUGCCAUGUGAGACAACUCACUCUUUCUUUGCCUUGUGCAAAGAUUGAAAGAUUUCUGAGGCCUCCCAGAAUAAGAAGCCCUGUGCUUCCUGUCCACCCUGCAGAACCAUGAGCCAAUUAAACCUCUUUUUCAAAAUGAAUCAAACAGAAAAUGGCAAAUGACGAUUGCAGCAUUGCUAUAAAGAUACCUGAAAAUGUGGAGGCAGCUUUGGAACUAGGUAAUGGGCAGAGGUUGGAAGAGUUUGGAGGGCUGAAAAGAAGACAAUGAGAAAAUUUUUGGACUAUCUUAGAGACUGGUUAAAUGGUUGUGAUAAAAAUCCUGGCACAAACAUGGAUAGUGAAGGCCAGGCUGAGGAGGUCUCAGAUAGAAAUAAGAAGCUUUCUGGAAAAGGUCUUCCUUUUGAAUAUGGAAAGCUUACACAAUGCCUGUACCAUCGUUAUACGUUAGAAGCUGUGAACUUGCUUUUUAUUUCAGAGGCUCAUAGGAAAAAGAGACUGUAGCCUUGACUCAGAUGAGAUUUUGGACUUUC